GAGGAAGCGGCAUCAGGGGUCCCUCAGGUGAAGCGCUCGCGGUGGGGAGGCAGGAAGUCGAGCAUGCGGCCCUCUCGCAACCAGGGUGUGAAGCGCAGGUUCAGGGAUCGCCUCUAACUUCCCAGGACAGCCAACCAUGGAGCCCGUGGGCAGGAAGCGCAGCAGGAAGGCUGCCAAAGCUCAGUUGGAAGCUCAAGUUACGGCCGCCCAGGGGGCCACGAAAGAAGGUUCAGGGAUCGCCUCUAACUUCCCAGGACAGCCAACCAUGGAGCCCGUGGGCAGGAAGCGCAGCAGGAAGGCUGCCAAAGCUCAGUUGGAAGCUCAAGUUAGGGCCGCCCCGGCGAAGAAGCACACAGGAAAGGAUCCAGUCCGUGAUGAAUGUGAGGAAAGAAACCCUUUUACAGAAACAAGGGAGGAAGAUGUAACUGAUGAGCAUGGGGAAAGAGAACCUUUUGCUGAAAAAGAUGAACACACGGGGAUUCAUACCAUGAAGCUAGAACAUAUUGCAGCUGACAUUAAAAAGGGCCUUGCUGCAAAAAGAGAAAUGAUAAAAAUAGAUAAAGCAGCUUACAGGAAAACCAAGAACACAAUUGAACGUGCUUUGAAAAAAAAACAACUAAAAAGGCAGAAACGUGAUUAUAGACAUACUCGGAAGUUGCUGAAUGUCCUUAAAGAAUACAUCGCAGAGAAGCAGAAAGAUGAUGAAGCAGAAGAAGCAGAAGCCGCAGCAGCAGCAGCAGAAGCCGCAGCAGCAGCAGAAGCCGCAGCAGCAGCAGCAGAAGUAAUAGUAGUAGAAGACGAAGAGGAGGAAGAGAAGGAGGAGGAGGAGGAGAAAGAAGAGGAGGAAGAAGAAGGAGAAGAAGAAGGAGGAGGAGAAGAAGGAGAAGAAGGAGGAGGAGGAGGAGAAGGAGAAGAAACAGAAGAAGAGGAAGAGGAAGAAGAAGAAGAGGAAGAGGAAGAACAAAUUAAAGCAUUUCAAGAAAAACAGAAGAGGUGGCAACAACCUACAGGUGUUAGGAGCUGGAGGCUGAGAGAGAUGAAGCCGCUACUUGAGCAAUUACUAAAGGCUGCCAAGGACACUAAAGACAAUUAUUGCAUCAUUUCUUCCAGUGAAGAAAGUGAACUUGAUAACUAGCCGUGUUUUUAAAAAGAAUCGUGUCAGAACUCUUUUGGAAGAGUUGGCACUUCAUUGUCUCUUCAACCUCUGUUAUUCUGAUGACUGAAGAAAGAACUUGAACCUAUGUUAUAUGAUACGAGCACAACUUGAGCUACAGUAAACUACAUGACAGUGUUUUGAUAAUUGUUGUAUAAAUCGGUAUAGCUCCUCUGUCACUUGUCUGUUAAAUGCCAGACCUCGUUUCUAUGAUCUGUUGAAUGAAUCCUAGACACUUCUGUGAGAAGGCAGGGAUUGCACAGUUAUGUACAUGGUCAAUUAAAUUUUAACAUUAAAGAUAAUUUAGAUUUCAGUUCACCUCUGUGGAUCUGUAUCAGUUUCAAAAACGUAGAAAGCACGGGCAUAGAAAAGUACAUUUUUCUCUAAUAAA